ACUUUAAGCACGGUCUGUGAAAUGGCGGGGGACUUACAAAAUGGUGCAGAUUGGACUUUCUUGCCUUCUACUUUAAUAUAAAAGGAAGAGGGGCGUUGUUGAUUAUCUGGCUGUUUCCUGUCGAAUUAGGGGCACUGUAACCAGGGUUUGGGUUUUGAAGUAGUGGGUGUUCGACUUUAGAGUUGUUUUCCUGGAAGCGCUGAUACUGGACUUAGUGGAGGAGAACGACGGUAUCAAUGUGUUUCUGGAUGACUGCCUGGACAAGGGAGUUCAGCUUUUGGGAGACUGACUGGGCUAUGAAGUGUACCUUUCUACUCUGCAGAGGCUGGAAAGGCAAAAAUGAUGGCUAAGGCUUCCUUGCAGCCGCUGAUACAGAAGCCUGAGGGAACACACUCCCCCCUACGUCCUUCUCCAACACAGCAGAGCCAGGAAGGACCCGGAUGGAAGUUAGGACAAAGAGGCCCAGAAUUGGCACAGAUACCAACAGACCAUUCGUUGAAGAAGAAAUCCAAAUGGCCAUAAGCUUUAAGAUUCUGGAGGCCAAGAAUUUGACUCCCCCCGGAUCCAUGGUCUGUGGAUACCAAUGUUCCGACUGGAGACGGGGAGCCCGCGAGACCCGGGUCUCCAGGGUCUGCCCAAGGAAGUUGCUCAUGGGAGCAGACCUCUAGAGCAGGAUUUGAGGCCAGGCCAAAGAGGGAGAGAAUUCGCCGACAUCUAUUUAACAUCCCUUAAUUGUUGAGAGCAUCCACUGUGUGCCAGACACUUCGGUACACACAGAAAGAAACCCAGAGGAGGGUUGCUCACAGCCUGGUGGGAGAGACAUUGCAACACAAUGUGAUUGGUGCUGUGAAGAGAGAGAGCACACGGUACUGGGAGAGCUCAGGGCAGGGGGUUGAUCCAGUUCCGGGCAGGGCGAUGGAUUCACAAGACAUUUUGGCAAAGAACCCCAGAGAUGAAAGGCCUCCUCCCACUGGCUUGGUUCCUGGCUUGUAGUGUGCCUGCUGUGCAAGGAGGCUUGCUGGACCUAAAAUCAAUGAUCGAGAAGGUGACAGGGAAGAACGCCCUGACAAACUACGGCUUCUACGGCUGUUACUGCGGCUGGGGCGGCCGAGGAACCCCCAAGGAUGGCACCGAUUGGUGCUGUUGGGCGCAUGACCACUGCUAUGGGCGGCUGGAGGAGAAGGGCUGCAACAUUCGCACACAGUCCUACAAAUACAGAUUCGCGUGGGGCGUGGUCACCUGCGAGCCCGGGCCCUUCUGCCAUGUGAACCUCUGUGCCUGUGACCGGAAGCUCGUCUACUGCCUCAAGAGAAACCUACGGAGCUACAACCCACAGUACCAAUACUUUCCCAACAUCCUCUGCUCCUAGGCCUCCCCAGCGAGCUCCUCCCAGACCAAGACUUUUGUUCUGUUUUUCUACAACACAGAGUACUGACUCUGCCUGGUUCCUGAGAGAGGCUCCUAAGUCACAGACCUCAGUCUUUCUCGAAGCUUGGCGGACCCCCAGGGCCACACUGUACCCUCCAGCGAGUCCCAGGAGAGUGACUCUGGUCAUAGGACUUGGUAGGGUCCCAGGGUCCCUAGGCCUCCACUUCUGAGGGCAGCCCCUCUGGUGCCAAGAGCUCUCCUCCAACUCAGGGUUGGCUGUGUCUCUUUUCUUCUCUGAAGACAGCGUCCUGGCUCCAGUUGGAACACUUUCCUGAGAUGCACUUACUUCUCAGCUUCUGCGAUCAGAUUAUCAUCACCACCACCCUCCAGAGAAUUUUUACGCAAGAAGAGCCAAAUUGACUCUCUAAAUCUGGUGUAUGGGUAUUAAAUAAAAUUCAUUCUCAAGGCUAAUAAAAACCACAUUGGCAUUUUCCUCUGCUGUGGGGGAUCGCUGGUGCCUCUUUCUCUGCCACUGGGGCAAUAAACCCAAAGAUGUCUACAUUAUCUCCGAAACAGAAGGGAAGAUUAGUAAAUGCAGGGUUUUCUGGGAUGAGCUUCAGGCUUUCUCUUGGGCUAAUUUUCUUACACCUUGGGGUCCUCUCCAGUAUUGGGUCUCAUUCUUCCUCGAUGGGGUCAGGGAAAGAUAACUGGUGAUUAUGCCAGCUUCAGCUUCCAGGCCAGAGAGGGUGGCAUUCAAAUCCCAGUGCUGGCUUCUUCAGCUGUGUGGUCUUGGACCCGUUACUGAACCUCUUUGACUUUCAGUCUCUUUGAGAAAUAAACUGUCUUGUUCCUUGCAAUGUAAAAUGAGACUUCUAAAGCCCACCUUGAUGCUGAUAUGGAGAAUGCUGAGGUUCUAGGAUUUCACACAGCAGGAAUUUUUUUUUAAUAGGUGUCAGCUGUGGGGUUUAUUUUUUACAAAGUAAGGACAUUAAAAAAACCAACCCGUCUAUCAAUUCAUAAAAGAAAGGAUGUUCUGAUACCAAGACUGAAAGAAGAAAGGAUGUAUUCCAAAACAAAGGAACAUCCUUCCAAGAAAGGACCUAUGGCUUCUUUAUUCCGACAUACCCCAAAAUAACUGCAUGAUAAAUAGGUCUAUAUUUAAAAAGCUCUAGUGUCGAAUGUUUUCAAAAUAAAAUUUAAUUUUAUGAGAUUACCCUGAA